GGCCUCAGCCUCCCAAAGCAUUGGGAUUACGGGUGUGAGCCACUACAUCUGGCCUCACUCGAUUUUGUACAAAAGUCACAAUCAUUGCUUUUUAUUCCUGAGUCAUACUCCUGUUGUGCCCCAUGUCUGUGGGACUACACUGACAAAUAGUUUCAUGCCCUCAGGAACAAGUAGCUCCAUGGGUAACAAAGUAAGUGCUGCUGUAAAGGACAAAAGCAGAAAUGCAGGGUAGUGUGGAGAGAAUAGAUGGGGAAGCUCAAUGGAGAUUAGGGCAAUCAGGGAAGGCCUCCCAGAGGAGGUGACAUUUUGGCUAAAACCUAAAGGAUGAAGAAGAGUUUGCCAGCCCAAGAAUGGGAAGAAAGAAGGCUCCGGGCAUAGGAAACAGUGUGUGCAAAGGCCUGGAGGAUCAGAGCUCGGUUUUUGUUUUGUUUUGUUUUAGGAAAUGAGAGGCCAGUGUGGCUGAACCAGUGAGGGAUUCAGGGAGGGAUUUCCAGGUAAGGCAGGUGUGGAGCAGGCAGGGACUAGAUCAUGCAAUGCCUUGGAGGCAGUGGGAGGAUGAGGCCUCAUUGCUGGGCACUGGGCAGGAAAGGAAGGAAGAGAGAUAGGAGGGCAGGCCUUGUGAGUGAACCUGACCCUGCAAGUCACAUGGCGAGGUGGCAGCAGCUCAGCCCCAGGGCACCCCCCGGGGAGAUGCAGCUUGCCCAAGGUCCACCUCCACUGGGCAGACACCUCUGCCUGGCUGUCUCCGUUUCCCCAGAGGAGGAGCAGGAGCCACGCCUAUGGUCGCAUGUUGCUAACCAUCUCGAGGUCAGGAAGAUGCUCUGUGAGACGGAGUGGGUCAGAUGCCAAAGAAAACACAAGCUUGUCAGCGGUGAUGUCUCCCUGCAAAGGCAGCCGCCACCAGCUUCCUGCCGAGAUGGGCCGGCUCAGCCUCACUUGCUACAGCUGGAGAUGGAGAGGACCAGAUGGCCCUGUUUGGCCCAGAUUCCAGCCAGAUUGCCAGGGAGGUGUAGGCGGAGCAGCGGGGUCGGCGCCAGGAGCAGGGAUACUACGCUACUUCCUGAAGAAUAAGGUCAGCCCUGAUUUGUGCAAUGAGGACGGACUCACAGCCCUACACCAGUGCUGCAUCGACAACUUUGAGGAAAUUGUGAAGCUGCUCCUCUCCCAUGGUGCCAAUGUGAACGCCAAGGACAACGAGCUGUGGACACCUCUCCAUGCUGCAGCCACCUGCGGCCACAUCAACCUGGUGAAGAUCCUCGUUCAGUAUGGGGCCGACUUGCUUGCUGUCAACUCGGAUGGGAACAUGCCAUAUGACCUCUGCGAGGAUGAACCCACCCUGGAUGUCAUCGAGACCUGCAUGGCAUACCAGGGCAUCACCCAAGAGAAAAUCAACGAGAUGCGGGUGGCUCCUGAGCAGCAGAUGAUUGCGGACAUCCACUGCAUGAUCGCAGCGGGCCAGGACCUGGACUGGAUAGAUGCCCAGGGUGCCACACUGCUGCACAUAGCUGGAGCCAAUGGAUACCUGCGGGCAGCUGAGCUCCUCCUGGACCAUGGAGUGCGUGUGGAUGUGAAGGACUGGGAUGGCUGGGAGCCCCUGCAUGCAGCUGCCUUCUGGGGACAGAUGCAGAUGGCAGAGCUAUUGGUGUCCCAUGGAGCUAGUCUCAGUGCAAGGACAUCCAUGGAUGAGAUGCCAAUAGACCUGUGCGAGGAGGAAGAGUUCAAGGUCCUGCUGCUGGAGCUAAAACACAAGCAUGAUGUGAUCAUGAAGUCACAGCUGAGGCACAAGUCAUCCUUGAGCCGGAGGACCUCCAGCGCAGGCAGCCGUGGGAAGGUGGUGCGGCGAGCCAGCCUGUCGGACAGGACCAACCUGUAUAGGAAGGAGUAUGAGGGAGAGGCCAUCCUGUGGCAGCGGAGUGCAGCUGAGGAUCAGCGGACCUCCACCUACAACGGGGACAUCAGGGAGACCAGGACAGACCAAGAGAAUAAGGACCCUAACCCCAGGCUGGAGAAGCCCGUGCUACUCUCCGAAUUUCCUACCAAGAUCCCACGAGGUGAACUGGACAUGCCUGUUGAGAAUGGCCUCCGGGCUCCGGUCAGUGCCUACCAGUAUGCGCUGGCCAACGGGGAUGUCUGGAAGGUGCAUGAGGUGCCUGACUACAGCAUGGCCUAUGGCAACCCUGGCGUGGCCGACGCCACCCCGCCCUGGAGCAGCUACAAGGAACAGAGCCCUCAGACGCUUCUGGAGCUGAAGCGGCAGCGGGCUGCAGCCAAGCUGCUCAGCCACCCCUUCCUUAGCACACACCUGGGCAGCAGCAUGGCCAGGACGGGCGAGAGUAGCAGUGAAGGCAAGGCCCCCUUGAUCGGAGGCAGAACUUCACCGUACAGCAGCAAUGGGACCUCGGUAUAUUACACGGUCACCAGCGGAGAUCCCCCACUCUUAAAGUUCAAGGCCCCCAUAGAGGAGAUGGAGGAGAAGGUGCAUGGCUGUUGCCGUAUCUCCUAGUCUCCGUGUGAUGGAGGAGGGAGAUGCCUGGGGAGGGGCUCCUGGAAUCCAGGCCAGCCCAACAGCCCUGGCUGGGGAGGUGUCAGGGCAGCUGGGGAGAGGUGGGCUCUGCUUUUCAGAGGAACUCAGACCCCAGCCCUCAGCUGGCUGCCCAUAGCAUCCCAUGUCCCACGUCCCGUGGUUCUGCUUCCUGCUGCAUCGUCUGCCAUCUGACACAAGGCCUGUCGUGGCCUCCUGGUUCACUCUGCUGUCUGAUCUUGGGAGGGUGGGCUUGAGAUCCCAGCUCUAUUCUUGGUAUAAAGGCUUCUCCGGAUCAGUACAUGCAUGUCACAUUAACACACACACACACACACAUAUACACACACACACAAGCUCGAUCAGUGUGUGUAGGAAUGACAUACCUGGGCUCAGGGGAAGCAAGGGGGCUUAGAAUUUGUGGGGUAUUCCCAAAAGGAUGGAAGUUAAGACUCAGAGUCUCAUUACCACUGCCAAUGUGGUUUUAGCAGGGGAGGGGACCUGCUAAGCUGAGACCCAUAGUCCUGCUCAGAGUUAUCCCAAAGUCUGAGCCACCAGCCACACCUGACAGGGGUGAGAAGUCCUCGCUGUGUUCAGAGGGAGCCAGGAAUCUACAUGGGUAGAUGAGAUAGACACAGACCUGCUCCCCGCAGCCUUGUUGAGAGCCACACUUCUGCCCAUGCCAGGAGCCAGCUGUGUGACCAUCCAGGGGUGGAGGGGGAAAACCAGGCAAUUUCGUUCCUGGAAUCAACCAAAUCAUGUUUUCCUCUUGGAUGGAAGUGUCAAAGGCAGAAGGGUGUGGGAGGGGGACAAGGUCAGUAUUUACCAAAGUGUAUCUGAUUUUAAAAAUUCCUUUAGUCUGUAAAACUCCUAGAGGGAGGGAGGUAACUGAAUUCACUUCUUUUUGUGGAUCGUAUCAAGGUCACUGGGUUUUACUGGCUGGUGCUGGGAAAAUGAAGCUAAGUGAGGAGCUUCCAUUGGAAUGCUUUUCCAGGGAGAGAGGCCAGUUAAUUUAAAAAAAACAGUCGCUAGUUAACAGCGACAGAGCCCAGCACCCUGGGGUCUUUGUGAAUAUCCAGACUGUUUCAGCCCAGCCCAUCUCAGCCAACCCUCCUUAGACUGAGCUGUCAGAGCAAGCAAUUAGGGGCCAGCCUGCCUCCACCUCCCACCCCCUUCCACCUCCAUCAGUCAUGUGUGCAGAGUCAGUGCUCGGGAUCCCGGGCCCAGCUUUUGCCUUUUUGGGGAUGCUUGGUGAGACAGAUUUGCCAGUCAGCCCUUUUGAGUUCCCGCCUCACCCAGGGGCUCCCAGCCUGCACUUGCAGGAGUGGUGAUGCCCCAAGUCUGCGAAUCCAGGGUGCACGUGGUCAAUAUCCCCUCCUGCAUUCAGGAGAGCCAUGGUAGGGCUAGAGUUGGGUCUUGCCCAGCCCUGCAGUUUCAUAGUCCCAGCCUUCCUGGUGCUGGGGAGGGAGGACUGUGAAUGGCUGUUCUCCCCUCACUGCUGAGUCUCCCAGGACCCCCUUUGGAGAUGCCCAUGGCAUGGGCACUGCCCACAGGCUCAGCCAGAACCUCUUGGUGUACCCGAUAAGCUGCAGGUUAUCCCUUGCUCUGUGCGCCUUUUAUUUGUCCUUAAACUACCUCCUUAGAGCUCUGAAGGGGUCUCCUAGUUCCAGAUUUUAAUUUGGGGAACAGAUCUGGGUUCUUUUUAACCCUCUUCUUUCUCAGUCUAUGAGAAACUUGCCCUGAGGGGCACCUGGGCUAGGGGCUUGGGACUGGAAGACCAUCCCCGCCUUGUGCCACAACUUUGGUCAUGGGAUCUGCUCUUUGUCAUUCUUAGCCCCCUACUGUGGCCCCCAUAGCCCCAUAACCCAGAGAGGGAGCUGGACUUCAGGGAGCCUGAGUGAUGCUUUCCCAGGAGCAGGGCAGCUGGCUGGACCAGAAAGUAGAGGGCCCAUGGGAGUGACUGCACCCUUGGUGGCUGCUGGAAGGGGAGAGGUUCUCAGCAUCAGGCCACCUCCACCCCAAUGCCAGGAUAGAUGUAUUCUAGAGUAGGGGUGGAGGCGGCCCAGGAGGCUGAAGACAGGUGCACAGAUGCUUCCCACGACCUUGCCAUUUGGGGUGGGCUCUUCAACAUCUCAGGCUGUGGCUGGAACAGGACAGGAUGAUCUAAAACACACGUACCAUUGGCUGUAAAACAGUAUGAGCCCAGACUGACGCUGAAAUCCCUCAUGAGCCAACCUUAGCUACAAGGUAGGGAGUUCUGAGGGAAGCCGCGUGCUCCUCAGGAGAGAGCUGUUUAGGUUUUCCGAUCUUUUUGCUCAGGGGCCAAACACUGAAGGCACGUACUGCCCAACCCACUGAGCGCCUGAGGCCAUUCCCUCCUUUUCCGCAUGCCUCCUGCCUCCUGGGCUAUUCCUCUCCACCCAGAAGGCUGGGAAUCCCAGCUGAUUCCCUGACAGGAGCCGACUUCACACACAGGUGACUCUCAGGCAUUGGCUCAUGUUUUCAGCCAGGGAUAAACCAUCCCUUCUUGGGGCUUUAAGUCCCUGGGGAGCUUUCCCUGUAGGUCUCCUGGGUGUUGAGAGACAAGUUGGAGACCAACCUCCAAUGAAUGAGCCGCGGUCAUUCAUUAAUUCACUCACGUAAUUUACUGAGUAGCUGCAACAUGCCAGCCUCUACGUUAGGUUCUGCGGAUAAAGGAGGAAUAAGACAGAGUCAGGAGAACUGUUCCUUGUGGUUUCCGUCCCUUGGGGACCACAGGCAUCAGCAGUCCCAUUCAAGUCACCUGAGGCAAAGUGUCUGCAUCUUCGUCCAGCGACCCUUUGCUUUUCGGCUCCUAGAAUCCUUAGAGUCUGAAUUCCUUUAGCUGGGAACAGCUGUCAUGGUCACCCCUGGAUAACAUUUGCCACCAAGUAUAGAUGCUGGAUCUUGGGUUCCAGGCAGACAUCAUCCAGGUCCAUCUGGAACUUUCAGUGAUAGCUGCCUUCAGCCAGCAUCUUUGGGGGACUCUAUAAUAGCAGCUUGAGAUCAGUGUCUAGAAGACUGUUCUGCAAUUUGCUGCCAAAUGCAUCUCAGGUUUUUAAAGUCAUUGUUUCUUGCUCAUGGUGGCUCAUUUAUUACAUAGUCCCCUCACCCCACUAAUGGAUAAUGGGAGGAAAAGUUGCUGCUUCCUUCAGCAUCAAAGCCUUUCCUUGGGAAUCUGCCUCCCUCCAUGGCAGGGGUGGAUUCGGGAGCUGGGAGUAACCAGGCAAAGUCAACCAGAUGCCUAGCUCCUGCUGAGACCCAGGUCCUAUGGCAGCUCCUCAUUAGAUUAAAGGAGACCACUUCCAAAGCAGGUGCUGCAUGGCUCACCAUCAUAUGCCCCAAACAACUGAAAGUUGGCGGUUAUCACCAGACUGUGAGUUUCUGGCAAGUAGCUUGGGGAAGCUGAAUAAACUCUAGGCCCAGGGCUACUAAAGACUUCAGGAUAGAAUUCUCCAUCAAAUAUACAGCAUAAGUAAAACUGCUCUGCACUGUUUAAUCCAUUUCCAAGGGGCUUAGAAAAGCUAACAAGGGUGUGUCCCCUGUCCUGCCCCACCGGUUUGCUGGCUUUGUAAUAACAUAAGACCAUUGUGGUUGUUGGUGUCAGAUACCUUCCCAUCCUGAGCUCUCUCACCUACCUGCUCUCUCUCCUAGAGCAGGAUACUGGGGUACUUUUAAGAAGGGUGCUCCUUUUAAGAUGCCCAGAAAAGCUGUAUUUAACUCUUGCUAUUUGUAACUUGGGGAUGGUCUCCCCUGCCCCAGGGCACAUAAGAGCAAAGGCUCCAAUGGUCAGUGGAUGACUCUGCAAAAGUGACCCCCUGUGCCAGAAGCUAUAGCCCUCUCCCCAACAGGUCUCUCUUGUUGGCCAGAGGGCCUGCUUCCCAUGGGCAUUGCAAGUGCCACCGUGCGGGGCCUGGCUCUGCACACCCAGGAAAAGUCUGCAGACCCCCAGCCCUCCGCAAUAAUUCACCAGACCAGAAGCCACUGGUGUACAGAGAACACUUAAAAAAAUGUAUUUUAUGUGAAAAAAAAUUAAAACUCUGUAUACUGUAUCAGCAGCUUUGUGUAAAAAUGGCAAUCAAGAGAGUCUAAUAUAUUUAAAACUUUUUUAAAAAAAAUCUUCGCAGAUCUUUGAUAUCGUACUGAGGUAACUUCCACGUAGCCCCUUGCCACGCGGCACCGGUGGGCCUUGGGUCCAAAACUGUGGCUCAGCCACAUCCCAAAGGGGGCACAUGUCCCUGGAGUUGCUUCCAGCUGCCAAGGCCUGUGACAGAAUUCGCUGUUAAGAGUUUUUAAUUAAAAUUAUUAAAUUCCUUUUAAUAACA